AACAAAUGGAAAGUUUGUGGCAACCCUACACUGAAAAAGUCCAUAGGCACCAUUUUUCCAACAGCAUCUGCUCACUUUGUGUCUUUAUGUCACAUUUUGGUAAUUCUUAGAGUAUUUCAGAGGUUUUCAUUAUUAUAUCUGUUGUGGUGAUUUUUGAUUAGUGAUCUUUGUUGUUAUUAUUGUAAUCAUUUUGAGGUACCACAAACUUGUGCCCAUACAAGACGGCAAGUUUAAUCAAUAAAUGUCUUUUCUGACUGCUCCGCCGACCAGCCGUUUCCCUGUCUCUCUCCCUCUCCUCGGGUAUCCCUGUUCCCCAAGAUACAACACAUACACCACCACACUCUGCUAAGCAACAGUAUUGAAAGGAUGCAAAUUAAUAACCCUACAGUGGCCUCUAAGCAUUCAAGUGAAAGGAAGAGUCAUGUGUCUCUCACUUAAAAGCUAGAAAAGAUAACGCUUAGUGAGGAAGGCAUGUCGAAAGCAGAGAUGGGCCAAAAGCUGGGCUUCUUGCGCCAUAUAACUUGAAAAGUUCUGAAUGGCAAGGAAGAGUUCUUGAAGGAAGCUACUCCAGUGAACACACAAAUGAUAAGAAAGCAGAACAGCUUUAUUGCUGACAAGACAGUUUUAGUAGUCUGCAUAGAUCAAACCAACCACAACGUUCCCUUAAGUCCAGCCUAAUCAAGAGCAGGGCCCUAACUCGUCAAUGCUAUGAAGGCUGAGAGAGGUGAGGAAGCUGCAGAAGAAAAGUUUGAAGCUAGCAGAGAUUGGUUCAGGAGGUUUAAGGAAACAAGCCAUCUCCACAAUGUAAAAACAAGUGUUGUUGUAGAAGCUGCAGCAAGUUAUCCAGAGGAUCUAGCUAAGACCGUUGAUGAAGGUGGCUACACUAAAAAACAGAUUUGCAAUGCAGACAAAACAGCCUUCUAUUGGAAGAAGAUGCCAUCUAAGACUUUCAUAGGUAGAGAGAAGUCAGUGCCUGACUUUAAAGCGUCAAAGAACAGACUGACUUUGUUAGUAGGUGAUAGUGCAGCUAGUAACUUUAAGUUGAAGCCAAUGUUCAGUUACCAUUCUGAAAAUUCUAGGACCCUUAAGAAUUACACUAAAUCUAUUCUGCCUCUGCUCUAUACAUGGAACAACAAAGGCUGGAUGACAGCAUAUCUGUUUACAACAUGGUUUAUUGAAUAAUUUAAUUCCACUGUUGAGACUUGCUGCUUAAUAAAAAAGAUUCCUUUCAAAAUAUUACUUUUCAUUGAGAAUGCACCUGGUUACCCAAGAGCUGUGAUGGAGGUGUGUGAUGAGAAUAAUGUUUUCAUGCCUGCAAAUGCAACAUUUAUUCUGCAGCCCAUGAAUCAAAGAGUAAUUUUGACUGUCAAGUCUUAUUUAAGAAAUACAUUUCAUAAGGCCAUAGUUGCUGGGUCUGACCCACAGACCCCGACCAAGCGAUGGAUGAACGGAUGCACUCAGACACAGGUAUCCAGUGAGAGUGGGCUAGGAGACUCGGCUGCUCAUGUACCCCAAGGAGGGUGUUGUAAAGAGUUGUAGCAGCUGUGGCCCUGACAAGCUGGUGCUGCAGGCAUUUAUUUAUACAGAUUUAAUGACAAAGGCCUUGAGUCAACACACUUUUGGGUAAUUAACAUGGUGCUUCCCCCCUUCCCCACCCCACACACACACACAGCCCCAGCAGUCCUGCACUCAGAUGAUUAAAGGCCAGGUUCUACUAAGUAAACUAAGUUAUCUAGAUCAGUUUCUUUACAUCUCCUUGUUAUCUAACCUAAGCGUUCAGGCACAGGGUGAGAGAAUCUGGCUGCCUUCAGCCAAAUCCUUUUCUGAAGCUUUUGUAAAAUCUCCCGGCCUUCCAAGAAGGUUUGCAUCUUUCUACAAUUUUUCCCACCACAGUGACCAAUCUCCUACACAUAGCUCCCAUAGACAGUGAUUCCUUUGGUGGAUCUGAGCAAAGUAACAGAGUUUCACCAUUCUAGAUGCCAUUAAGAACAUUUCUGAUUCAUGGGAGGAGGUCAAAACAUUGACAGGAGUUUGGAAGAAGCUGAGUUCAACUGCAGAUGUGGUAGCAAUAGCAAGAGAACUAGAAUUAGAAGUGGAGCCUGAAGAUAUGGCUGAAUUGCUGCAAUCUUAAGAUAAAACUUGAAUGGAUGAGUAGUUACUUCUUAUGGAUGGGGAAAGAAAAUAGUUUCUUGAGACAGACUCUGCUCCUUGUGAGGAUGCUAUGAACACAGUUGAAAUGACAACAAAAAAUUUAGAAUAAUCCAUAAACCUAGUUGAUAAAGCAGUGGCAAGGGGUUUGAGAGGAUUGGCUUCAAUUUCGAAAAAAGUUCUACUCUGGGUAAGAUGCCAUCAAACAGCAUUGCAUGCUGUAGAGAAAUCUUUCAUGAAAGGAAGAGUUGAUGUGGCAAACUUCAUUUUUGUCUUAUUUUAAGAAAUUGCGACAGCCACUCCAGCAGCCACCACCCUGAACGAUCAGCAGCCAUCAACACUAAGGCAAGACCCUCCACCAGCAAAAAAAUUACGAUUCGCUGAAGGCAAAGAUGAUUGGUAGAAUUUUUUAGCAGUAAAAUUUUUAAAUUAAGGUAUAUACAUUACUUUUAAAGACAAUGCUGUUGCGUACACACUGCUGUAUAGUAUCAACAUAACUUUUAUUUGUACUGGGAAUCCAAAAUAUUUAUGACUCAUUUUACUGAAUAUUUGCUUUAUUUUGGUAGUCAGGAACCACACCUGCAGUAUCUCUGAGGUAUGCCUGUAGCGAAACUUCAUUUUUUUAAAGAACAACAAUAUAGUAGACAUAAAAGUUAGGUGCUAUGCAUUUAUUUUAGUAAUGAUAUCAUUUUGAGAAACAUUUUUGGAAUUUUAUUUUAGACUUCUCUUGAGUUUGGCUUUUUUUCCCAUUAACAUUAACUUAUUUUUUGUGAUCUUUAUGCUUGUUUGAUUUGUAGAAUUGUUCCACCAUAAAUAUUUAAAUACUUUUAACUACUAGAUUUCUUUUUUCUUUUGUCAGACGAAGUCUCACUUUUGUCCCCCAGGGUGGAGUGCAGUGGUGCGAUCUCAGCUCACUGCAACCUCCACCUCCCGGGUUCAAGCAAUUCUCCUGCCUCAGCCUCCCGAGUAGCUGGGAUUACAGGUGCCUGCCACCACAGCCGGCUAAUUUUUGUAUUUUAAGUAGAGACAGGGUUUCACCAUGUUGGCCAGGCUGGUCUCAAAACUCCUGACCUCAGGUGAUCCCCCCACCUUGGCCUCCCAAAGUGCUAGGAUUACAGGUGUGAGCCACCAUGUCCAGCCUUAACUACUAGAUUUCUUUUGCAGUAUUUGGAAUAUUAUUUUAAGUAAUUAAAUGAUCAAUCAUAGCUACUACAUUCUUUUUUUGCCUUAUUAAAACCUACCCUUUAAGAUCAGGAAUAAAACAAGGAUGCCUGUUGUUACCUUCCUUUUUCAAUAUGUUAUUAAUACUAGAAAUCUUCGCAAGGUAGCUGAAUUUAAAAUCAACAAAUAAAAAUACAGGUGCAUUUUUGUAAAUCAGCAAUAAAAUACCAUUUCAGGUAGGAAAAAAUUAAAGUAACAAGUAUUUUCUAACAAAAUUGUGUUAAACCUUUAAAAGAAAAUUAUAAAAUUUUAUUGGAAGAUGUUAGGAAAGGUCUAAAUAAAUGGAGAGAGAAUAUUUUUAUAGAUUUAAAGAUGCUUUUGGAAAGAUAGCAGAUCUCUCCAGUUAUUUAUAGAUUUAUUUCAAUCUAGUCAGAAUCAUGACAACUUUUAUUUUUGGGUUAAAAAGUUGAUUCUAAAAUUUUUGAGGAAGACUUAACAGGUCAGGAGUAGCCAAGACACUCCUCUAAAGAAGUUGUGAUAGGUGAGAAGACUUGUUUUACCAUAUAUGAAGAAUUAGUAUAAAGCUGUAAAAGUUAAGACAACAGUAUGGUAUAGGGAGAGAUAGAUCAAUAGAAGAGAAUAUGGAAACCCAGAAACUUGGCUUGUGACAAAGUUGGUAUUACACUCCUUUAGAGAGAGCUUUCCAUAAAUAGUUCUUGGACAGCUGGUUAUCCACAUAGGAGGGAAUGACAUUGAAUCCCUGCUUAAAUGGGAAAAGCAAACCUUUAACAUUUUUAGAUAUUAAAACAUUAUAAUGAUUUCUAGAUAGAGAAGAUUUUCUUAAAACAUAGAAAAUAUGAACCGUAAAAGAUGCUACUUUUUUUGUUUUAGAGAUGGGGGUCUUGCUAUGUUGCCUAAGUUGGUCUUGAACUUCUGGCCUCAAGCAAUCCUCCCACCUUGGCUUCCCAAAGUAUUGGGACUAUAGGCAUUAGCCACCAUACCCAGACAAAGAUACUUCUUUUUUAUUAAGAACAUUGGGAAAAGGGCUUGGGAUGGUGGCUCAUACCUGUAAUCCCAGCACUUUGGGAGGCUGAGGUGGGAGGAUUGCCUGAGCCCAGGAGUAUGAGACCAGCCUGGCCAAUAUGGUGAAACCCUCUCUUUGCAAAAAAAAUACAAAAAUUAGGCGGGCAUGAUGGCGUGUGCCUGUAGUCCUAGCUCGGAGGCUGAAGUGGGAAGGAUUCAUUGAGCCCAGGAGGUUGAGGCUUCAGUGAGCCAUGAUUGUGCCACUGCAUUCCAACCUGGGCAACAGAGGGAGACCCUGUCUCCAAAACGCUGGGAAAAGAUACUGCAGUACAUUUAACUCACACAAGGCUACAUUAGGAUCUUCACAGACUAACAAGAAAAACACAAAACAACACAUCUAGUAGAGCAGAACUUCAGUAGGCAUAUUAGAGAAGAGGAAAUGGAAUGAUCAGUAAUGCCAGAGAUGGUGGGGAAAUGCAAAUUAAAACUAUAUUAAGAUACCAAUUACAUCAGAUUGUCAAAAAUAAAAAUGUCUGACAGUAAUAAGUGUUGUCAACGAUAUAACACAUCCACCACGUGCAGUGAUAUAACAGUUCACAUCUGGUGGGUGGUUUCAGCCACCUGGGAAAACAAAUUGGUGAUAUCUGAUCAUAUUGAAAAUAUGCAUACUGUGCCACCUAACAACCAUACGUAUAUACUUUAGAUCAGGGGUCGGUGUGAUGACUCAUGAGUUAAGAAUGGUUUUUAACAUUUUUAAGUGCUUAAAAAAAAUAAUAUUUUGUAAUUUAUAGUGUGAAAAUUAUAUGAAAUUCAAAUUUUGGUGUCCAAAAAUAAGCUUGGAAUAUUGUCACAUUCAUUUAUGUACCUCUUACAGAUGCUUUCAUGGUACAACACUAGAGUUAAGUUGUUGCAACAGACAUUGCAUGACUCAAAAAGCCUGAAAUCUUUAUCAUCUGGCCCUUUGCAGAAAAUAUUUACUGACCUCUUCUCUAAAUAAAUACUCUUGCACAUGCGUACUAGUAGACAUGUUCAGGAAUGGUCAUAGCAGUAUUGCUUGUAAUAACGGAAACCUAGAAAGAACCCAAAUGUCUGUUAAGAGUAGAGAAAUAGGUUUGCUAAGCCAGCGGAAUACUAUUCAGUAGUGAAAUGGAAUUGGAUGCAUGGAUGGAUCCAAGCAUAUGGAUAAAUCUCAGAAACAGUGUUAGAAAAAAGCAAGUCAGGUUUUUCCACUUAUAAGCACUUCAGAAACAGUCAAGUAUAAAUAAGGCAUUGUUAAAGAUACUCGUGAGGUUAAAUUAUCAGGACAAGGAAGGACCGUAAGAAUAGGGAUUGCCUUUGAAGAGUUGGGGAAGAGAUGGGAUUUGAGAGGGAACUUUAAAAAUCAUGUUCUUAUUGUUAAACCAGGUGGUGGAGAUGUGUGUUGUGUUGUGAUCAUUUAUUUCCGUGACAUGUUUUAUACGUACUCUUUUGAUAUUUUAUAAGUUUUUGUGAUCUGGGGCAUUAAAAAGUAUCUUUUCAAAUAGUAUAGUCUGUCUCAUAAUAUAUAAUUAUGACCCACAGAGUGGAAGCUCAUCAGCAGACUAGAAGCUGCUUUUUACCUAUUGCCCCCUCUUCCCUGGUUCCCCAAGCAUUCUGGUUGUGUCAGGAACCCAAUUCAGAUUUUCUUAAGCAGAAAAGGGGACUAAUAGGAUUCCUCGUUGGGUCACUGAAGCCAAGGAAGAGUCAGGGACUUGGUCACUGUCAGGGUGCUCUGCCACUCAUCUGUAUGUCUCUGCUUGGCCACAUUGUUUUUGGCUGCAAGUGGCCUUCUCCAUGUCGGGGGCAGUGUGACUGAGCGCAGUCCUAGAGCACAGCCUUCCAGGUCUGUGACUCAGGCCAAGGAGUCAGGUCCUGUGGUCAGCCUGGCUAGGUCAUACUGUGGCCAGGCAACUGGAUCUGUUACCAGAAGAAACCUUUUGAGGAGGGGAGGAGAGGUUAAGGGUCAGAAUCAUGAGCCCGGCAGCCACUUCUGUUUGUAAUGGUUACAUAUGUAUUAAUUGUAAAGCAAUAUGUGUGGCAUUUUGUCACACCUUUGUGUGGAUAUCAGGGCUGUUUUGAUGUUAACGCUAAGAUGUUGCCUAAGACAUGGCACUGAGACAUGGCCGAGGUGGGAAGAGGGGUUAGAAAUGUCUGUUGAGCAUAUUAUUACCUGUUAAAAAUAAAAAUACAGCAUGAUCAGCUCUCCUACCACUUUAUAGUCACACCUGUCUCCUUCCCUUCUUCCCAUAAGGACAUUUAAGGCAUUAAGUACUUGAGUCUAAAUAGAUGUUACAAACUUGGUUUAAAACAUAACACAUAUCUGGCUGGGCACGGUGGCUCACGCCUGUAAUCCCAACACUUUGGGAGGCCGAGGCAGGCAGAUCACGAGGUCAGGAGAUCGAGACCAUCCUGGCUACCACAGUGAAACCCCAUCUCUACAAAUUCAAAAAAUGAGCAGGGCGUGGUGGCAGGCACCUGUAGUCCCAGCUACUCGGGAGGCUGAUGGCAGGCACCUGUAGUCCCAGCUACUCGGGAGGCUGAGGCAGGAGAAUGGCGUGAACCGGGGAGGUGGAGCUUGCAGUGAGCCGAGAUCGUGCCACUACACUCCAGCCUGGGCAACAGAGUGAGACUGACUCAAAAAAAAAAAAAGAAAAAAAAACACAUAUCUACUAUUCUGAAUGACUGGAAGGGCAUUUAACCCAUUGGUGUUUCAUUGGGAUGCAAAUUUGUAGGGAGUUUGUAUCUUUUGCUUUUCUGUUUGCCAGGUUCUUUGUUUUGAACAUACAUUACUUUACAAACAGGAAAAAUAUAAACUUUUAAAGGUAUUGGUGGAAGUCAGUUUGUCAUCUUAAAAACUGACAUUCCACUCAAGACACUAAACACUGUAUUCUCUAAUUUGAAACAUUCGAGCCAAUAAAUUUUAUAGGAGUUUAUUUACAUCAUGACUACCCCAAAUGAUAAGCUUGUUCUUCUGACCUCUAAACUUGAGAUAACACCCGGGAAAUAACUACAGAAAGAGAAUAUCCAGGUUUUAAUGGAAUGUGGACAUCAAUCUGGGCAGGAAUUUUGGAUUGAUUAUUUGCUAAUUUUUUGUUAAAUACUUAUGUUGAAUAAGAAGAUUCCAAGACCUGAAAAUUGGUUCUCCUUUUUCUUUGGCUAUCGAAUAAGGCUUCUCAGUGCUAAAUUUCGAUCAGUAACCACUUGACAGCUCAAAAACUGUGGCAGAAGUAUUGGCCUGAACACUUUAUAGGAAGCUGGGAAUAUAAAUUGAAGCCUACGAGACUGGAGCCGUACUCACUUUGGCUACUAGGGGGUAUGAACGUGAUUUCUGAUGAAACUGGAUUGGAAUAAUUUUCAUGAUCUUUGUAUAUUUAUAUAUAUAUAUUUUUAAAUUUUGCAUUUGACUUAAAGUGCCAUGAGAAAAUUUGCAUACUGCAAGGUGGUCCUAGCCACCUCCUUGAUUUGGGUACUCUUGGAUAUGUUCCUGCUGCUUUACUUCAGUGAAUGCAACAAAUGUGAUGAAAAAAAGGAGAGAGGACUUCCUGCUGGAGAUGUUCUAGAGCCAGUACAAAAGCCUCAUGAAGGUCCUGGAGAAAUGGGGAAACCAGUCGUCAUUCCUAAAGAGGAUCAAGAAAAGAUGAAAGAGAUGUUUAAAAUCAAUCAGUUCAAUUUAAUGGCAAGUGAGAUGAUUGCACUCAACAGAUCUUUACCAGAUGUUAGGUUAGAAGGGUGUAAAACAAAGGUGUAUCCAGAUAAUCUUCCUACAACAAGUGUGGUGAUUGUUUUCCACAAUGAGGCUUGGAGCACACUUCUGCGAACUGUCCAUAGUGUCAUUAAUCGCUCACCAAGACACAUGAUAGAAGAAAUUGUUCUAGUAGAUGAUGCCAGUGAAAGAGACUUUUUGAAAAGGCCUUUAGAGAGUUAUGUGAAAAAACUAAAAGUACCAGUUCAUGUAAUUCGAAUGGAACAACGUUCUGGAUUGAUCAGAGCUAGAUUAAAAGGAGCUGCUGUGUCUAAAGGCCAAGUGAUCACCUUCCUGGAUGCCCAUUGUGAGUGUACAGUGGGAUGGCUGGAGCCUCUCUUGGCCAGGAUCAAACAUGACAGGAGAACAGUGGUGUGUCCCAUCAUCGAUGUGAUCAGUGAUGAUACUUUUGAGUACAUGGCAGGCUCUGAUAUGACCUAUGGUGGGUUCAACUGGAAGCUCAAUUUUCGCUGGUAUCCUGUUCCCCAAAGAGAAAUGGACAGAAGGAAAGGUGAUCGGACUCUUCCUGUCAGGACACCUACCAUGGCAGGAGGCCUUUUUUCAAUAGACAGAGAUUACUUUCAGGAAAUUGGAACAUAUGAUGCUGGAAUGGAUAUUUGGGGAGGAGAAAACCUAGAAAUUUCCUUUAGGAUUUGGCAGUGUGGAGGAACUUUGGAAAUUGUUACAUGCUCACAUGUUGGACAUGUGUUUCGGAAAGCUACACCUUACACGUUUCCAGGAGGCACAGGGCAGAUUAUCAAUAAAAAUAACAGACGACUUGCAGAAGUGUGGAUGGAUGAAUUCAAGAAUUUCUUCUAUAUAAUUUCUCCAGGUGUUACAAAGGUAGAUUAUGGAGAUAUAUCGUCAAGAGUUGGUCUAAGACACAAACUACAAUGCAAACCUUUUUCCUGGUACCUAGAGAAUAUAUAUCCUGAUUCUCAAAUUCCACGUCACUAUUUCUCAUUGGGAGAGAUACGAAAUGUGGAAACGAAUCAGUGUCUAGAUAACAUGGCUAGAAAAGAGAAUGAAAAAGUUGGAAUUUUUAAUUGCCAUGGUAUGGGGGGUAAUCAGGUUUUCUCUUAUACUGCCAACAAAGAAAUUAGAACAGAUGACCUUUGCUUGGAUGUUUCCAAACUUAAUGGCCCAGUUACAAUGCUCAAAUGCCACCACCUAAAAGGCAACCAACUCUGGGAGUAUGACCCAGUGAAAUUAACCCUGCAGCAUGUGAACAGUAAUCAGUGCCUGGAUAAAGCCACAGAAGAGGAUAGCCAGGUGCCCAGCAUUAGAGACUGCAAUGGAAGUCGGUCCCAGCAGUGGCUUCUUCGAAACGUCACCCUGCCAGAAAUAUUCUGAGACCAAAUUUACAAAAAAACGAAAAAAAUAAGGAUUGACUGGGCUACCUCAGCAUACAUUUCUGCCACAUUCUUAAGUAGCAAAAAAGGAAAAGUGCUUUCCUCCUCUGCAGGAUGUAAGGUUUAUCAGCCAUUAAAACUUAGACUUCUCUAGCUUUUCACUAGCUGUGAACCAGCCUUCCUGUCCAUGGACGUGAAACUGCAUAGUAAUGAGACUGUGCACACUGAUGUUUACAAGAUUGAAAGAGUCUUUCUCCGAAAAUCAUGGUAAAGAAUACUGAGACAAUGAAAAAAAAUCAACAAAAUAUGCUUUCUGGAGAACUGUACCUUUUAUGGUUUGCUUGCACAUCAGUAGUUUCUGCUGAACGUGCUGUCAUAAUGAAGAGAUUUCCAAGAUUUUUUUUCCUGAUUAGAACUGGUAGCCAGUAUAUUAAAUAUUGAUAUAAAAAUAAAAGAACUGGAACCAGAUUCAGAAUCAUGAAAACAACAUUUUUACAACAACAAAAAAACUAUAUUAAACAGGGUUUAAAGGAAAUUAAAACAGAACUAUGAGAAGUACAAUUUGUUAUAGUAUAGUAUCAAAUUUCUAUAUAGAUUUUAUACCUCAGUGGGGAAAAAUAACUGAUUCCAAUGACAUUCAUUUUGUUUUCAUCUGUGAUAGUCAUGGAUGCUUUUAUUUUCCUUGGGGUGCUGAAAUUGAGCUGAAAAAAAAAGGCUCUUUGAAUAUAGUUUUAAUUUCUCUCUACAGUUUUUUUUGUUUGGUUUGUGGGCUGUUGGAAUUGUAAUUUUUAAUUGCCUUCUAAAAAAUGGAAAUUUAACAAUGUCUGAUCUCAGCUGAACAAAUUAGAUGUUUCAGUUGCUCUUGGGUCAACUGGCUUACAGAUUUACAUGUGCACACACACACAAAUUUCUUAUCACAUUUUCGACUUCUUCACUUGACCUAACUGAUUAUGCGAAAUACCCAAGAUUCAUGCUACUGUACCACAGAUUUGUUUUCACAGCAAUAAAUCUUCAGUUCUUUGUUUAUGAUUCCACUUAACAAAAGGCCUGCAGAAGUGAUUUAUUAUUUGGGUAUUUGGAGAUAAUACAUUUGAUGGUUUUUUGGAAAACCUUUUUCACUCCAUACUCAGAUAUGCUUCAUUGUCAAAUGCAUAUUUAGAUUAGAUUAUUGAAUUGUAAUGUUUAUCUGCUGCUUUUUUUAAAUAAAAUUUGACUGAAAAUGUUUAAUUGGCAUUUUUUAAUGACUUAGCCAAAGAAGUGCAGCUAUUAUUCCAUAUUAAUAGGCUUGCAUUUCUUUUCCUAAAUCUUAUUUAGGCUAAAUCAGUUUUAUUUUUCUCUGAUUUUUUUUAAUACCACAGAAUCACCUGAGUGUCAAUUGAAAGUUGUCAAUUAAAAGGUAACCUUUUAAUCUCGUAGGAGGAAUCUCAUUAAGACAUUUUUCCUGAUAUGUAGAGCAGUCUGUUGGCAAAAAUGCAUAUAUUUUCUUUCAUAUUUGUAAAAUUAUAUUUAAUGGAAUUCUUUUCUUUGAUUAUCAAGGACUUUCACUGCAGGCAGUGCUAUUUCUUGUGCCUAAGAAUGUUUCCAAAAGUCGCAUCGCUAAUGAUAUUUGCCAAGUUGAGUGUACACAAAGUUUCUCAUAUCCUGUUCAAGUUAAUCAACAUCAAGCACAUGGGGAUGCUUUAGGGUGAGUCUAUAGUACAAAAUGCAUAAACCAUGUCCCCAGGAAAUUUGAAAGGAAGCAGGUGCUGAAUGGAAUUUUUUUCCUUUUCCAUGAGCUGUGUUAAUUCUAUCUCCAGUAGGCCUAAUGCUUGAAUAAGCAAGAUGUCUAAUCAAUAAAUUAUUUUCAUGCUCAGAAUUUCAGGUUUUUGUACUCCAGCAUAGCUUGGUCUUAUUUCUUACUGUAUGAAAGCUUAACAGCAAUGUGAUUUAAGGUUUUGUUUUAAAUGGGAGAUGUAAGUGAUUUAAUUCAUGGGUACUUUUAGAACCUGAUAGAUAAUCCCAUUGCCUUUAUUUUUCUAAUUAAAGAAUUCCUAAAUACUUUGAAAAUACAAAAUAUUCCUGAAUA